GUUAGGGAACAAUUCUCCCUUGCCUGGGAGGUACAGUUCUGACAUCUGCUACCGAGAUGGAAGUUUGUCUGGAGUAGCUCAGGUACCUUUUAGGAUUUGGUGAAAGGAGGAGGGUGAGCGUUGGGAGUGGGUGGUGCUGUAAAGCCAUAUUGGCUUCUGGGGUCAUCGGGGGACCAUGGAUAAAGAAGUCCUUGCCCUUUUUUAUUUCACUUCUUGGAAGCUGGGAGUUUUGCCCUCAGUGAGGGCCAAGGUGGCGGUUUGUGCAUAUGCCCCUGGUCCCCUGACUCUAGAGGGAGGGUCUGGUCCUUUUCCUUGCGUUUUUUGUAUUUUAUUUUUGGUCGUCUCCUCACUUGGCAGAACUUCUGCAAGCUGUCUGACCUCACCAGGGUAGAGGCCUUUACUCCCUUCCCCCUUUCUGUUUGAUGUUCUCGUGACUUUUAUUCCUUGGCAAAUAAAGAUGCCAGGCUUGAAACAAGUUACUGUUGAGGGAUGGUUCUUAACUUCCUCUGCCCACCCGCCCCUGUUUAAAAAAUUUAAAGGCAGCAGUCCGUGGAUUAUUAACUUGACAUGGUCUGGGCAAACAUGAAAUUAUGCAAUCCUCAGUGUUCCUAGAGAACCACCCGGGCUGGGAGUGUGCCCUGCUCUGACAAAAGGAAGACGCCCUGUGGGGGAAAGUCGAGACGGCCUUGCACCCUUAUUUUUCGGCAGUGGAUGGUGACGGGGGAGGCCCACACAGGGCAGGUUUUCCAGUGAUGUGCUCGCUCUGCCCAUCUUCAAGCAGGAGGAACCCCAGCUGUCCCCCGAGAACGAGGCCCGCCUGCCACCCCUGCAAUAUGUGUUGUGUGCUGCCACGUCCCCAGCCGUGAAGCUGCAUGAAGAGACGCUGACCUACCUCAACCAAGGUCAGUCUUAUGAAAUCCGACUACUGGAGAAUCGGAAGCUGGGAGACUUUCAAGAUCUGAACACAAAAUAUGUCAAGAGCAUCAUCCGUGUGGUCUUCCAUGACCGCCGGCUGCAGUAUACGGAGCACCAGCAGCUGGAGGGCUGGCGGUGGAGUCGGCCAGGGGACCGGAUCCUGGACAUCGAUAUUCCACUGUCUGUUGGUAUCUUGGACCCCAGGGCCAGCCCGACCCAGCUGAAUGCAGUCGAGUUUUUGUGGGACCCUGCGAAGAGAGCUUCUGCAUUCAUUCAGGUACACUGCAUCAGCACAGAAUUCACCCCCAGGAAGCACGGGGGCGAGAAGGGAGUGCCCUUUCGAGUCCAGAUUGACACGUUUAAGCAGAACGAGAAUGGGGAGUACACGGAGCACCUGCACUCAGCCAGCUGCCAGAUCAAGGUGUUCAAGCCGAAGGGAGCCGAUCGGAAACAGAAGACUGACCGGGAGAAGAUGGAGAAAAGAACUGCCCAAGAGAAGGAGAAAUACCAGCCGUCCUAUGAAACCACCAUCCUCACAGAGUGCUCUCCAUGGCCCGACGUGGCCUACCAGGUGAACAGCGCCCCGUCCCCAAGCUACAAUGGUUCUCCAAACAGCUUUGGCCUCGGCGAAGGCAACGCCUCUCCGACCCACCCGGUGGAGGCCCUGCCCGUGGGCAGUGACCACCUGCUCCCAUCAGCUUCGAUCCAGGAUGCCCAGCAGUGGCUUCACCGCAACAGGUUCUCGCAGUUCUGCCGGCUCUUUGCCAGCUUCUCAGGUGCUGACUUGCUGAAGAUGUCCCGAGAUGAUUUGGUCCAGAUCUGUGGUCCCGCAGAUGGGAUCCGGCUCUUCAACGCCAUCAAAGGCCGGAAUGUGAGGCCAAAGAUGACCAUUUAUGUCUGUCAGGAGCUGGAGCAGAAUCGAGUGCCCCUGCAGCAGAAGCGGGACGGCAGUGGAGACAGCAACCUGUCUGUGUACCACGCCAUCUUCCUGGAAGAGCUGACCACCUUGGAGCUGAUUGAGAAGAUCGCCAACCUGUACAGCAUCUCCCCCCAGCACAUCCACCGAGUCUACCGGCAGGGCCCCACGGGCAUCCAUGUGGUGGUGAGCAACGAGAUGGUGCAGAACUUCCAAGAUGAAUCCUGUUUUGUCCUCAGCACAAUUAAAGCUGAGAGCAAUGAUGGCUACCACAUCAUCCUGAAAUGUGGACUCUGAGCAGCAGUGGACCUCAUACCUGUCUCCAGCUCCCAGCCCUGUGGAUCCCCGUGGAUGUAGACAUUGCCCCACUGUAAGCUGUGGCCUCACCAGGCAAGCUGAGGCCAGGAGGGACCCUGCCCAGUCUGUGAAAGCUACAGAGCACCAACCAGCAGAAGCCUGUGGACACCAAGUACGGUGUACAGAAAGCCAGUGGCUCCUUUCUCCCUUCCUCUUGGCCUCCAGAUUUUGAAUGGUUCCUUGUUCUUUUCUAUUGGUCCAACCCUGACGUUCUAAAAGGGCAAACAGUGGAGACGUCUGCUCUGAAAUCCCUCAUCCCUUAGUUGGAAGCUGAUUGGGUAUCUUGGUGCUGCCUGUAUUGGUCCCUUCUGACCACUCUCCUGCCUCCAGAGAAAGCUCUGCUUCACCCUGGAAGCUGGUACCUUUACCUCCUCCUCUGGGAGUUGGCUGCAUGGCCAGCACUGCCGACUUGAUGGGAGCAGUUUGCCCUCAUUCUCCUGUUUCAGGUUUGCUUCCCUUCUCAGUGACCCUGGUGAGCAUCCGCCUUUCCUGUUCUUGGAUGAAUUGAUGGGAGUGGGGCUAUUCUGUGCCUUCUACCUCUUUCUUCUCUACGUUGUUUCUAAGGAUCUGCUGCUGCGGAACCCAAAGAUGUGCUCCUGUCUCUGCACUGGCGCAUUGGCAUGGUAGAUGCCACAAUGUAUGUGCACGGCCUUUCUCAGAGACAUUAGUUCUGAGGCCCUUUGUGGGGAGGUUAGGGGGAUGGUAAUAGAAAAAGACUAUUUUAUUUCCUGGCAAUCACGGGUAAGGAGGAUUAGGAAUGAGUAUUCCAUUCCUAGGUGUCAUCAGAUGACCUUGACCACCACAAUACCAGGCCCUCUUGGAUGGACUUAUAGAAAGUUAGAGAAGACCUUGUUGAACCGCUGCUAAACUUGCCACAGGAGCGAUGUGUUUUCUCUGAGUGCCCCUCACUUACAUGUUUAUCUUUGUUUGUAGAGGCUAUGUUUAGGAUAUUUUGCCUGCAUCAGAAUGGGUGCAUCAUCUUUCUUAAUGGCCUAACUAUCGGGAAAUUUGAGUGUCAGUAACUGUGGUAGACUCAGAAAUUCGUCUUUGUCUUGCCUCUGGUUCCUGGGAUCCAGUGAUCUCUACUGGCCCAGGGCUUCAGCUCUUGGUUAAUUUAGGUUCAUGGGGAACCCUCUGACCACCUGAAUGGGAUGUCAUAGCUUCUAAAUGGAGCUUCUGUGGAAUGAAGUGCUAGACUGAAGGACUACCAGAAUAAAACAGGGUCUACAAUGGGGAGAACUUGUUUUAUAGAUGAGGAAACCAAGGCUCAGAGGGGCAAAGUCACCUGCAUGGUAGCACAUAGUGAUAGGGUAGCGAUAUAAAUUUAUCAUAUAAACCAGGACAUCUCGGAAUAAAAGGGGCUCUGUUAGUCAUUAUGUUGGGUAAUAGCCGUGGCAUUCCUACAGAACAGAGUGAGGACAGGCUCCUGAUUCCUCUUCCUUCUUUAGAGGAGAAGCGGGGAGUGGGUUAACUAACAGCUUUAUUGAGAUGUCAUUCACAUGCCAUUCAGUUUACCCAUUGCUAGUGUCCAAUUGUAUUCACAGAACCACCAUCAAUUCACAGAAUUACAGUCAACGUUGGUACAUUUUCAUCACCCCCAGUAAAACCCCGUACCCUUGGUCUGUCACUCCUGCUUUCCUAACUCCUGCAGUCCAAGGCAGCCAUGAAUCUACUUUCUAUGUAAGAUUAACCUACUCUGGACAUUUCAUAUAUCUGGAAUCAUGUGAUAUCUCUUUUGUGACUGGCUUCUUCCACUGAAUGUUUUCUAGGGCCGUCCAAGUUGAGGAUGUAUCAGUACUUCAUUCUUUUGUAUUGCUGAAUAAUACUUCAUUGUAUAGAUAGACCACAUUUGUUUAUUGAUUCAUCAGUUGAUGGACAUUUGUGUGUUUUUACUUUUUGGCUACUCUGAAUGAUGCUGCUAUGAACAUAUUUCUACAAGAUUUUGUGUGGACAUAUGUUUUCAUUUCUUUUAGCAAUAUACAUAGGAGUGGAAUUGCUAGGUCUUACAGUAACUCCGUGUUUUAACUUUUUGAGAAACUGCCAGACUGUUUUCUAUAGCAGCUGUACCAUUUUACAUUCCCACCAGCAAUGUAUCCAGGUUUCAAUUUGUCUACAUCCUCAUCAACACUUGCUAUUAUCUGUCUUUUUGCUUUUAGCAUCCUAAUGAGUAUGAAAUGCUAUCUUGUGGUUUUGAUUUGCAUUCCCCUGAUGGCAACUGAUGCUGAGUGUCUUUUCCUGUGCUUACGGGCCAUGCGUAUUUCUUUGGAGAAAGGUCUAUCCAGGUCCUUUGCCUAUUUUUAAUUGAGUUGUCUUUUUUUUUUUAAGUUUUCUGUUUUCCUAACCACUAGACUACCAGGGAUGAGCCUUCUUUUUAUUAUUGAGUUGGGUGAGCUAUUUGUAUAUUCUAGACGCCAGUCUUUUAUCAGGUAUAUGACUGGUAAAAAUGUUCUCCCCUUCUGUGGAUUGUUUUCAGUUUCUUGUUGGUGUCCUUUGAGACACAAAACUUUUUAACUUUGAUGAUUUCCAAGAUACGUAUUUUUUUUCUAUUGUCACUUGUGCUUUUGGUGCCAUAUCUAGAAAACCAUUGCCUAAUCCAAGGUCAAGAAGAUUAAUGCCUGUGUUUUCUUCUAAGAACUAUACUUUUAGUUCUCACAAUGGUCUUUGAUCCAUUUCGAGUAUAUUUUUAUAUAUGAUGUGAUGUAGGGGUCCAGCUUCAUUCUUUUGCUUGUGGAUCUCCACUUGUCCCACUGCUGAUUAUUGAGAAAAAUAUCCUUUCUCCACGGAAUUGUCUUGGCAUCCUUGCUAAAGGCCUCUGCUUCUUACUGGAUCUUCUUUCCUGGGACAUGGUGUCGUUGGGAAGCUUACCUUUUUUUUUUUUUUACUUAGUCUGUGUUUGGUUCCACCAGUUUUAUGCUGCCUUUCUACUCUGUUCUUGCUGUCUCCCUCUUUACCUGAGUCAACGGUACUGAGUCCUAUCUCUCUCUGAUGUUCCCCAGUCUUCCUUGGUGCAUGUUCUAGCUCCACACACUAGUCCUUGGAGGAAGGUUGAGACCAAUGAUUUCCUGUUAUGAGUCAUGAGGAAACUGAAUCACCUAGAAGUGGAAUAAUGUGCUCAGGGUCACCAUAGCCCAUUAGUGGAAGGACCAGGACUAGACCUUUAGUCUUCUGAGGUCCAGCCCCUUAGGCUGUCUGUCAUCACUGUACCCAAGUGAUGUCACUACCAAGGCCAAAUGAUGGUGGGCUAAAUUUUAAUUCUCAAAAGUGUAGGAGGCUAAUAUUGUCUUCUAAGUUCCAAAAGAAGAUGUAAUAAAAGUCUGUUACCUUAAGUGUGCUAUUAGUAGAGUCUUCCAUUUUUCUGGCAUGCCCCUGGCAUCUGCUCUUCUUACCUUCUCGUGGUUGUAGUUAAAGCUUAUAGCUUAUGAAAGAAUAGAAAAUAAUAAAUACCAAAAAAAAGUACACAUGGUAAUUUGGUACCAAAAUAUCUCAGCUGCCUAAUUUAGCAGCUCAUCCCUUCCACAGGGGUCAGAUGAGCUAAAGCUCCAGGUUUUAUUUUUCAUUUGAUUGACAUACAGAAAAGCCAUAGCCCUUCCCACAGCUGUCCAGGGUCUUUCCUGUGAGUCCGGAGGUGCUGGCCUAUUGAGCAGGACAGCUCUUCCCAGGGCAUUCCCACCAACCUGUGGCUUCUGAACUGUAGCUUCUUUUUACAGUGAACCCCAGAGGGAAAUAAGACAGACACAUGUGCUCAGGCCACCAUCUUGAACUGGAAGCCCAAAGCUGAGUUCCUUACUCUUAGGUCGUCACGGUUUUUGCGGGGUAUCUGCAAGGUUGAGAUAAACCCUUUCCUGUUUACCAGGUUGUCCUUUCUGGAUGAAGGGACAGAGGCUGUUGAAUGGAGGAAUAAUAGGUUUGCUGGAGGAGGGGCAUGGUAUGCCUGUGGAAAGGACAGGAUGGGGUGGGGAGGUCGAGGCUUUGACUUGGGGUCCUAAACAAAGGUCAGGUGUUGCCCUAGUGACCUCUUGCCCAGACAGCCCAGAGCCCCUUACACAGAGCUAUUAACCUAGGGAAGGCUUUACCAGCAGUGGACUGGAGCCAGCCAGGGUCACAAGUUUCCAAGUCCAGCAUUGCUUCAGGGGCUGGCCUGAGUAACUGAAGAUCUGAAAAUCAUUAACAAGUCGAUGAAAUAAACGGAAAAGCCUCUUAGGCUGUUGUCAGUGGAGCAGAGGGAGAAAGUCCCUAGGCGCUCAGAGGGGGUGAGAAAGCAGUGGAUGAUUGGGCGGGGGUGGGGGAUUAGAUGUUGACACUGCCUGGGGUGUAGGAAGAGGAACAGAGAACCCAGAGUCAGGGUCCUAGAUCCCAGACCCUCGCUCAGUAUGAGUCUCUUUGCCUCUCUGGGUCUCUAUCUCCUCCUCUUACAAAUACAGGCUUGGUGAUCUCUGAAGAUGGCACCAACCUGCCAUGAAAUGAAUCUGAGGGGUUUUCCCAUUUUUCCCUCCAUCAAAAUCGUACAAAAAGCUGGACGUGGUGGCCCAUGCCUCUAAUCCUAGCAUUUUGGGAGGCCGAGGUGGGAGAAUCACUUGACGCCAAGAGUUCGAGACCAGCCUGGGCAUCGUAGUGAGACUCCAUCUCUGUCUUUUUGAAAAUAAAAAAUCUUUGAAAAUUGCACAACAGGCAGGAGACCUUUACGUGUGCCCAUCCUGGUUGUACACAGUGCCACCAGUGCUCCUGCAGUGCAAGGCGGCAUGCUUCUUGACAUGGGUCAGAUUGUGUCCAUCGUGUCUUUGGGAAUCAGCCCUAGCUCCUAACUGGGCUGACUACUUCCUCCGCAAACUUAUGGGGGCUCCCAGAUAUUCCUUGCCAGCCAGGGGCCAGACACAGUGCAGGCACAGUCUGUGUCAUUGGUGCACAUGUGCGUGUUUACAUGUGUACCUGGGUUCCUUCCCUUGCCCAUGAAUUUGCCAUGAGCACAGCCAGAAGCAGCCUCAGCUUGGCAAGGUGUGGAGAUGACUGCUGUUCCCUUCGCAUUUGGGGAAAACAGGCUCCCUCGGUAGCUCGAUGAUCCUCUUUUGAUCUUGUGUGACCUCCUGGAGAGUGGAUGAAGCUGGUGGCCUUAGCUUUUCUAGACAGUGUAAGUGGCACUGGGCAAGGCCCCCAGAGCAGGGCAAGGUCUCUAGAGCGGGUCUCCCACAUGACUGGCUUCACACAGGCACUUCCGCUCGGGUUGCAUGCUCUGUGUCAUCUUACCGGUCCAGGGUUGCAGGUAGGAAAUGUUUGUACCCUCUUCUGAUUGCCACCUCCUUCCCAUCGCCCCUUAGGGACAGGGCUUGAGGGCCAGUGAGGCGCUGGUCAGGCACCCCAGGCCUCCUUGGGACCUGCCCAGGGGCACCCUGAGAGCUCCUGAAACCCCCACUUAGCUUCCAGACCUUUCUGCAAAAGCUCCUCCUGGCUUUCCUCCCUCCCCCAAUCUAUGGGUCACAGCUAACAGAUCUGAGGGCAACUGCUGUGCUAGUGGCCAGGGCUGCACCUGCCAUCCCCGGCUCUGCCACUUUAGGGCCUUCUAGAGGCAGUGUCCUUAGGAAGUAGCUCUGAGGCAUGGGUUUUCUGCUCCUGUGCAGGGCAGCUGAUGGGAUAAGGUGGGGAAGGACGGUCAGUGCUUGGGCCCCAGCUGGCCAGCCUGGCGAUGGGGAAACCAAACCAUGUCCCCCAGCGAAGGGCCAGAGUGGGAACCUGUCCUCAUGCCCUUCGUCCUGAGGAGCCCUGAGGUGGGCAGCAGGGGCCAGGGGAAGUUUUCAGGCCUUCAUCAAAGAGAACAACAUCCUCAGCUCCGCACCCCUCAUCCUGUAUCAGCACUUACCGGUGUGUGACUGCCCUUGUCAGCUAGCAUACGGUGGGCCCACCUGGCCCACUGGCUGUUUAUGCCACUGAUUUAUGAUAGGGAAUAUUAUCUUUGAACCCAAUGAAGUGUUUUCUCCCCCAUCACAAAAAAAAAAAUUCUUAUUUUUAGUAGACAUGUAUUUACCAAAAAUAUGUACUCAAUUAUUGUAUUUUGGAUUUUAUCAAUUUAAAAAUUGUGGAAAUUUGUUUGCUCUUACGCCAACAUAAUAUUGAUUUUGCCUCUUGGCUCUGAAAGCCCAAAAUAUUUACCGUCUAGCCCGUUACAGAAAAAGUCUGCUGACUACUGAGCCAGACCUCCAUUACCUCCAUCCCUGUUGGAUUAUUUAAAGAAAGCCUCAGACAGUAAGGGCUUUUUUAAAAGAAUAAAAUGACUUGGUUUGCGCUUGGAAGCAGGGGAAGCAUUCAGAUGAGCGGUUUCUGCAUUAACCCUGCCUAUCACGCAUCUCGUGUCCUGUGUGGCUGGCGAGCCCCCCUUGGAAGGUUCUGGUGCUUCAGCUGGCUCCUGCAGAGUCCACCCCGCCUCGUGGUGGGAAUGCAGAGCCCUUUGCUUUCCUUCUUGCCGCCUGCUUCCUGUUCCUGGGGACCCGCUGGGCCUUUGGUCUGCAUCCCCUGGCCAGGUCCCUCAGGGUUGAUGCGUGGAGAAGGACUUUGAGCAGUGGUGGGCAGCAGUGGCCUCCUGGCCAGCUCACACUCUUGUCCUGGGAGGGGCAGCCUGAUCUCACCUCCACCUAGUACCUUGGGGACUGAGGACCUUUUGGCUUCUCUGGAGCCUGCAAGCCUCUUCCCAUGUGUCCAGCUGCUCUUCCUGCUACAAAGGGGACUGCUCACAGUGGCCUCAGCUUGGUGGUUUUGAGGGGCCGCCCCCCGGCCCUCCAUAAGGGUAUCCUGGGCCUGAGAAUUCUGCAUCUGCCAUUGGAGGAUGGACAGCCUCAAAUGGAAGGAGUCCCACGGGAGAUGGGUCCGAGGUCCGGCUGUGGCCAUCCAGCCCCCUGUGGCUUGUCCAGCCUCUGUGCACCCCUGGUGUCUUCACUCCAGGGGCAGACAGCAGCCACUGCAGUUCCUUUCUUCGUGAGUAACAGUAGUGAUAGCAGCUGGGGCUAACAGGCUAGGCUUUGUGUUCUGCGCAUUUGGUCAGCUUCUCACUCGAUCCUCCCUAAAGCAAUGGGGAGGCCCCCACUAGCCCAGUUUUCAGGAAGUCAACUGGGAGGUUAGAUGGGGGCCAGGGUCCCACAGCUACUGAUGGCCCGAGCCAGGUUGAGCUUCCUGGUGUCCAGUCCGGAUCCCACUUGCAGAUCUCAUGCUCUCAGAUAGGUGGGACAAGUUCUUUUGUCACAGUGCUGGCUCUGUCCUGAGGCCUCAUUGCUGGCUGGGUGUGCUCUGCUGGGAAAAGCUUUGCGGGGCUUGCUUGGUUAACCACAGAAGAGAAGGGGACUGUUUGGGGUGCCUCUCUGCAGCCUCCCCGUGCUGGGUGGAAGCACGGUUACUGUGUUCUCUAAUGUUCAUGUAUUUAAAAUGAUUUCUUUCUAAAGAUGUAACCUCCACACCUUUCUCCAGAUUGGGUGACUCUUUUCUAAAGGUGGUGGGAGUAUCUGUCGGGGUGGUGUGGCCCUUGGAUGGGUCAGGUGGGUGUGAGAGGUCCUGGGGAGGUGGGCGUUGAGCUCAAAGUUGUCCUACUGCCAUGUUUUUGUACCUGAAAUAAAGCAUAUUUUGCACUUGUUACUGUACCAUAGUGCGGACGAGAAGUCUGUAUGUGGGAUCUGUGCUUGGGUUAGAAUGCAAAUAAAACUCACAUUUGUAAGAAA